ACUGGCGGCGGCAGCGGCGGAGGCGACGGUGGCGGCUCUCGGAGCCGGCGCGAAUCCGGCCCCCGCAGCGGGACCCGGGCAGGUCUUGACGAGCCCUGCCCGGGCCGACGCAUGCGGAGGAUGGAAACACUUGCCCGGCAAUGUCUCUGGGCCGCCUCCUUCGCAGGGCCUCCUCCAAAGCCUCGGACCUCCUGACCCUCACCCCCGGUGGCAGCGGCAGCGGGUCCCCCUCUGUCCUGGAUGGAGAGAUCAUCUACUCCAAGAACAAUGUCUGCGUGCACCCGCCGGAGGGGCUGCAGGGGCUGGGGGAGCACCACCCAGGUUACCUGUGCUUGUACAUGGAGAAGGAUGAGAUGCUGGGAGCCACCCUCAUCCUGGCAUGGGUCCCCAACUCUCGCAUCCAGAGGCAGGACGAGGAGGCCCUGCGCUACAUCACACCCGAGAGCUCCCCCGUUCGCAAGGCACCCCGCCCUCGGGGCCGGCGCACCCGGAGCUCAGGAGCCUCCCACCAGCCCUCCCCGACGGAGCUGCGGCCUACCCUGACCCCCAAAGAUGAGGACAUCCUGGUGGUGGCCCAGAGUGUUCCAGACCGCAUGCUCGCCAGCCCUGCGCCAGAGGAUGAGGAGAAGCUGGCGCAGGGCUUGGGGGUGGAUGGUGCCCAGCCAGCCUCGCAGCCUGCUUGCAGCCCCUCCGGGAUCUUGUCGACGGUCAGUCCGCAGGAUGUCACCGAGGAGGGGCGGGAGCCGCGGCCCGAGGCCGGGGAGGAGGAUGGCUCUUUGGAACUGUCAGCCGAGGGCGUGAGCAGAGACAGCUCCUUUGACUCAGACUCAGACACCUUCUCCUCGCCCUUCUGCCUCUCGCCCAUCAGCGCGGCGCUGGCCGAGAGCCGCGGCUCCGUGUUUCUGGAAAGUGACAGCAGCCCCCCGUCCAGCUCCGACGCCGGCCUGCGGUUCCCGGACAGCAACGGCCUCCUGCAGACCCCACGCUGGGACGAGCCGCAGCGGGUGUGCGCCCUGGAGCAGAUUUGCGGCGUGUUCCGCGUGGACCUGGGCCACAUGCGCUCCCUCCGCCUUUUCUUCAGCGACGAGGCCUGCACCAGCGGCCAGCUGGUCGUUGCCAGCCGAGAGAGCCAGUACAAGGUUUUCCACUUCCACCACGGCGGCCUGGACAAGCUGUCUGACGUGUUCCAGCAGUGGAAAUACUGCACCGAGAUGCAGCUCAAAGACCAGGUCGCCCCCGAUAAGACAUGCAUGCAGUUCUCCAUCCGCCGCCCCAAGCUGCCGUCCUCCGAGACGCACCCCGAGGAGAGCAUGUACAAGAGGCUCGGCGUCUCCGCCUGGCUCAACCACCUGAAUGAGCUGGGCCAGGUGGAGGAGGAGUACAAGCUGCGGAAGGCCAUUUUCUUUGGCGGUAUUGAUGUGUCAAUCCGCGGGGAGGUCUGGCCCUUCCUGCUGCGCUAUUACAGCCACGAGUCCACGUCGGAGGAGCGGGAGGCGCUGCGGCUGCAGAAGCGAAAGGAGUACUCUGAGAUCCAGCAGAAAAGGCUCUCCAUGACUCCCGAGGAGCACAGAGCGUUCUGGCGUAAUGUGCAGUUCACUGUGGACAAAGACGUGGUCCGGACAGAUCGGAACAACCAGUUCUUCCGGGGGGAAGACAAUCCCAAUGUGGAGAGCAUGAGGAGGAUCCUGCUGAACUACGCCGUGUACAACCCUGCCGUCGGCUAUUCCCAAGGGAUGUCGGACCUGGUGGCGCCCAUCUUGGCCGAGGUCCUGGAUGAGUCAGACACCUUCUGGUGCUUUGUGGGUUUGAUGCAGAACACGAUCUUCGUCAGCUCACCCCGGGACGAGGACAUGGAGAAACAACUGGAGGAGUGGACGUGGGAAACAGCCCCCAAGUGUGCACUGAGGGUGGGGAGCCUUCCUGGCCAUGGAGCGGCUGCCAGCGUCCUGCCACGCCCGGGCACAACACUCUGCCUCACCCUGGACCACACCACAGCCUCCGGAACAGUCAGAUCUGGGAGGAACUGGCAGAGGCAGCUGUACCUGCGCGAGCUGCUGCGGCUGACGCACGUGCGCUUCUACCAGCACCUGGUCUCGCUGGGCGAGGACGGCCUGCAGAUGCUCUUCUGCCACCGCUGGCUCCUUCUGUGCUUCAAGCGGGAGUUCCCCGAGGCCGAAGCGCUGCGGAUCUGGGAGGCCUGCUGGGCCCACUACCAGACGGACUACUUCCACCUUUUCAUCUGCGUGGCCAUCGUGGCCAUCUACGGGGAUGACGUCAUCGAGCAGCAGCUGGCCACGGACCAGAUGCUCCUGCACUUCGGAAACCUGGCCAUGCACAUGAACGGGGAGCUCGUUCUCCGGAAGGCGAGGAGUUUGCUGUACCAGUUCCGCCUCCUGCCCCGGAUCCCCUGCAGCCUGCACGAUCUGUGUAAGCUGUGCGGGUCAGGCAUGUGGGACAGCGGCUCCAUGCCCGCGGUGGAGUGCACCGGCCACCAUCCCGGCUCGGAGAGCUGUCCCUACGGGGGCACGGUGGAGAUGCCUUCCCCCAAGUCCCUGAGGGAAGGCAAGAAGGGCCCAAAGACGCCGCAGGACGGCUUCGGCUUCCGCAGAUAGGUCGGGCCCCCGACACCGGACAGGGGUUGAGGGGACCUCCUCAGAGGCCCUGGGCACGGGAGGGGGUGGGGCUGGGCGUGAAGGGGACAGGGGACGGUAGAAACCUAAGGAAAAUGCUUUUGGGCAACAUGAGAGGAACCUUUUCAUAUUAAUGACAAAAUUAGAGUCUGGAAGUGACAGAAGUCAGAUCUACAGCCACCCAGAGGAAAGUCAGCUCCUGAAACGCUGCAGUGGAACGCGCAGCCACCGCACCUGAGACGCAGGCUGGCUGGGCUCUCCUGCUGGCUGCCCUGGAGGAUUUCAACAUGUCCCAGGAUUUGCUCCACCCUCGAGGGCAGCCAGACAGCGUCGCCAGGCAAUGAGGAAAGCAGAGACAGGAGAGGAAGGCCUCACUCACCCACUGCGUCGAGGGCUGCAGAACACAGCGGGGUCCUGUCCAGGCCCAGGGACAUCUUUGCAAGCCAGACACACUUCCUCUUGAGACCUCGUUCUCUCGGAGUGAGCCAAACACACUUCCCAAAACGUCCCCAGCCACAGCUGGGAUGCCGAUGGAAAGGCAUCUGCCAUAAAAGAAAAGCAAAAGAUAAAAAGCCCAACCGAUGUGGGGAUAGAGAGGCGGAAGAGCAGUCAGGCUUGAGGAGCUGGCGCUUGUAAUGUUUAUCCGUUUAAACAUUUCGUCCUCCUGGUACACGAAGGGAACUGUCUGCCCAGGAGCCUGAGCCUCAGGCUGUUGGAGAAGCAUCUGAUGCCUUUUUCUUUGCUGGGGGUCUUCUACGUGAGGUUCCUUGGCGUUGUUUAAGGUCAACUCCACCAAAUACAGCAACCAGCUGGGGCUUGAAUGGGUCGAUGUGUGCGUGUGUCCCUGCGUGCAUGCAUGCAUGCACACGUGCGUGCGUGUUUGUGUUUGCAAGAUCCUCUGACAAUGAUCUGCUUUGUCCCAGGGACGUGGUAGUGUAUUAGCUGACCAACCAAGACAAGGACACCUGGAAAUAGUUAGACUCUUCCACUUCCCUUCAGGACCUGUGAACUCAGAUAUGUAAGUCAGCUUCUCAGGUGGUCGGACGUGAGAGCGACCACAGUGAAGGAGCCAGCACUCAGGGCUCUCUGCCUUCUAUGUGGGAAUGAGGUCUUCCCAACAGACUCUCCCUCUUCCAAAAGAUUGUGUAUCAGUUGCUCCUUCUGGGAUUUAGAGAUGGACAGAAAAGGGUGUGCGAUCUAUGCUGUGAGAACUCCCAGCCAGCUUAGAAGUGUCGAGCCAUUUGCACAGAAAGCCACUCCUUGAGCGAGGAGACCAAAUCCCUCCUGAAAUCCUCCAUCGCGUCCUUCUGGGGAGAAAAACCCUUGAUGUGCUGAGAACCAUCAUGGGGACCAGGAUAGAAGGCUUCUUCCCACUCAAAGCUUUUCUCCCUGGAGGGUGGGCACUGCUGGGCCAUGCCACUUCAAAGCAGUGUUCCUCAGCAGGAAAGCGGAGGUCACCACUUACCGGCCUCCUCCACCUUCUCGGCUUCUCUUUUCUCCAUGAACCCAGGUCGUCCAGCAGGUACUUCCAAGUUCCCAGGUCUGUCUGCCUAAGAGCCUUUUGAGGAGACCGUCCUGGAGCCCCAUCAGUGCCCAGAUCCUGGGGUACCGACCAUUGCUGUCUAGCAGUGGGGGAUCCUGUGGUGGGAAUGGGGUGGGCUUCUCAUCCAUGUUGCUUCUGGGAAGAGAGGGUUGCCUUUCUGGGCUAGGGAGGUGGCUGGAGCUUCUGCCCUGACCCUCCGCUAGAAACCAGUUAUAUCCAUUGCCACAGCAAUACUGUGUAACAAAUCCGCCAACACUCGGUGGCCUGCAACAGUCAGCACUGAUCUAGGGCAGGAGUCAGCAGUCUGGGCAGGGUGAUUCUUCUGGUCUAGGCUGGGCUUGUUUGUUUAGGGCCAGUGGGUUGUUAAGUCCCAGGGGAUGCUCAUGGUGCAGAGGUCGGACCUGGCCCUGCUCUGUGGUCUCUUGCAUCCCUCCUGCAGGCCAGCCAUGGCACAGCCAAAGGCACGGAGGGAGAGACAGCAAGUGCCUUUCCAAGCCUUGGUGGACACCACACCUGCAGCUCUCCCCUUGGCCACAGCAAGUCACGUGGCUGGGCUCAGCAUUAAGGGGUGGGGGACAGGCCUGCCACUUUAUUGUCCGCUCUGCACAGUCGGGUGGCAGUAGGCUGAGAAUUUGGAGGGCUAAACAACUGGGACUCUGGAGAGUCUGUGUCCUAAUAAUGCCUGCUUUGGAGCACUCCUUCCCCACCCGCCUGCUCCAGGGGAAUAGCGUCCCUGGUCCUAGCAUUUCACUAGAUACCUCGUGCCUUUGAACCGCUGUGUUUGGGAGGGAGGAAGAGGAUAGACAGGUCCAGGGCUCCCCUCACUUGGGAAGGUCCUAGUAGAAGGCAUUCCUUCUGAGUCUCCUGGCCCUACAGCUUCUCACCCCUGCUGCUCCCCAAGACCUGACCCGGACCAAUCAGCUGCAUCUCUGCACCAAGUGCCACCCCCACCGUGCACUGCUCGCACCUCACGCUCCCCAUGGGCUGGCCCGGACCCCAGUGAGGUCUGCACCUCUCGGACCAGCCAGGACCUCGGAAGCCAUGAGCUGGGUGUUCAGGGCUUGGCGGAGGAGACGCUGCUCCGCGGGGGAUGGAGAAGCCCCGCCCCUCCACAACUCCCUUAAUCUGGAUGCAAUUAGAGGAAACCAGCCAAAAACCCCGCGGCAGCUGUUGCCCCGGGAUUAUUCCCAGCCAGCGAGAGGCAUUAGGGCGAUAAUUCAGUCAUUAGACUUCUAGCCUUCCCACCGCCAGAACGUGCAAAUAGGGGAUAAUCAGCCCUGCACGGCCAUCCUCAGCAAUGCUGCUUAUUUAACCCAUUUUUUAAAAUGACACUUAAUGUUAUUGGCUGGCGUACGUGUGUGCGCAUACUUAAAAGUUGAUGCGUGGUGCAGCUCUGCUGCUAAUGUCUGCUGACAGCGUCGCCCGAUGUUGCUCAGGGCCUCUGGGAAGAGGGGACACCUUUGAUGUGGGCGUGCUGGCACCCAAGAGGCAACGUGGUCAGGCUCGAUGCUUGCCAGCCCUGGAAGGUCCCGCCAGGGUUGGGGGGUCGGGUGAGCACUCAGAGAUCUGGGGAGGAAGCGAGGAGCCUGGUGUCCUCACCAGGUGCAGAGGGGAAAUGCGUACUGCUCCAGAAGGUUCUGACUCAAGUCUCGGCCCUGAGGACUCAGAACUCACAAGUCAUGGAUCAAGUACAGAGGGAGGGAGGGCCCCAGCCCACCCCUGCGGGGGAGGAGGAGGGUCUGAAGGUGGGAGGGCAGCUCCAUGAGCAGCCACUGUUCCUGACCAGCCGAAGUGCCAGGCAGGGGGAGGUUUCCAUGUCCAGGAGGGAGAGGACCUCCACCCUCUGACCUUUCAGUUUUCCAUAGCAGCCCAGUGUGAAGCUCGGCGGGGGUGGGCAGGGCAUCAGGACAAGAUGAAGAUGCUGGCUCUGGAAUGAGGACUCCCCUUGGGCUAAGGGGUAGUGGCUGGCAGAGGUUGCCCAGCUCUUUUGGAGGCCACAGGGAAUAGAGGUGGGGUGGUGCUUCCGUUCCUGUGAGGCCCGCCCCCCUGAGCCCCCUCGUCUGCUUCUUGUUUGGCAGAAAUAGAUGUGGGGCACAGCCCCUAGAUGAUGGGAAUCUGCCCAAGCUGUGCCCUCUGGGGAAUGAAAUCUUGCUCCUCGUGCAGCUUCCCCUUUCCCUUGCGGGGUGGGGGCUGGGGGUGCCAAGGCUCCACCCUUGGAGGGGGUUGCUGGGGGUGCCAAGGCUCCACCCUUUGCUCGCUGGGCAGAGGGAAGGAAGCACCUCCCUGUAUGCUCUGCAGGGGCCCCUGCAGGCCACUUUGCCUCAGAGGAAGGAGGAGAGGUCCCCUGGGAAAAUGCGCACACACACACACACACACACACACACACACGCACAUGCACACACGCACGCAUGCACACACACACACACAUAUGUGCAGGGGUGCAGCCUAAGUCAGUGGAGCCAGGACUGGCUGCGCAGCUGGGCCUGCCCCAUUCUUGGAGUCCCCAGGGAAUGAGCCUCAGGAUCCACUUCGUCCCUUGUUUCUAAGCCAGGCUGCACGGCCGUUCCUGGGUGUGAAAGCAUUCUGUCCUGUCUCCAGUCAGAGGGAACCGCCCCCAAACUAGAAAGCUAAUUUCCCCCGAAGGUUCAUGAAGCCAGAGGCAUGCCCUUGGGGGUUGGUCGGGAGAAGGGUGAGAGGCAGUGCUGUGGAAGGGGCCUGGCCCCUGCUGCCUGCGAUUCUCCCCGGGUAUGUGGCCUUCUGCCUCCUUCAGCCUCAGUUUCCUCACCUGUAACAUGAGAAUAAUGAUGCCUGCCUGCCCAGGCCACCUCCUGGGAGUGCAUUGGGGACUCUAAGUGUAAAACUGUCAUGAGGAUGGUUUAUGAAGUCCCAGGGACCACACCUGCCACUCAGGGAAGAGACCGCUGACCUCAGCCAUCAGCCGUGUGCAUCGUGAGGGGCAGCGAGCUCAGGACGGAGAGCUCUCCCUUGGUUCGGAGUCAGCACACCUGCACUCCCACACGCCCACCCAGCUGUGUGUCCUCCGCCGAGGGCGAGCCUCUCUGUGACUCUUCUGUAAAAUGCACCCCAUUCUGCCCACUCCUGCCACGAGACCCAUCCUCUGCGAUCCCGCCAGGCAUGUGUGUGUGAAUGCAUGUGCAAAGCUCUCCAUCAGAAGGGUGGUGUGGGCCCUGCAGGUCCUACCCCUCGGCCUUGAAGCUCCCUCGGGCUGCGGACUCUGCCUCCUGGGUCUGAGCAUUAGAACCAGGAGAGGGGUGUCCCUGGGCAGAGCCAGGGGUGCAAACAGCCUGCAGCCAUCUGGCCUUUUAAGUAUAGUGUGUCGCAUUUCCGGGUAGGAAGGUAGCAUUUCAAGUUCAAAGAGAGGUCAAGUCAUGCAACCAUCUUUCCUCCAGCACUUUUGGGGUAAGGAGGACAGUUUUUGUUAUGGUUUAGGGGAAAUUUUCAUGAAAUUUCCACCAUUACCAAUAGAUUACUGAUGUCCAUGGCAAGUGAUCUGUUCUUGGUAUUUUGUUUUGUUUUGUUUUGGUUUUUAAAUGUAAUCACCCAUUGGUCAGGCCCAGGACUGGUCACCAUGAGCUCUGCUAGCCACGGCCCCAACGAUGCUUCCGGCUCUCAUGGAUUCCACAGCAAAUAAAACUGUACUGACAACAGAUGCACGCUGUACAGUGCCUCUGGAAGGUGCGGUGGGACUUGCUGGGUCAAAGCACGGCAGGCUCUGUGCUGGGCAAACAGGGCCCCGUGGCAGCCCAAGGGCAGCCUGCAGACGCCAGUGUGCCCGGCUUCUCCCAUGUUCUGAGAUGGGGGAGGGGAAGGUGUAAAAGAGAGCUGGAUGGGGGCUGUGGGGACUGAGGGUCCUGGGAGGCUGGCCAGGGGCUCAGCAAGCGCCCACUUUGGGAGGCCUUGCCCUCUGGGCUGUGGUUGGACAGCACUAGGCCUGCAGGCUGGGCUGCCAGGAGGAAGAGCAGCUCCGGACCUCAGGCCCCCCCAGCAGGCGGCGAUGGAGGGUGAUGGGAGAAUUGACGAGUGCUCGCGGGGUCUCACUCGGGAAAGGGCCGGUUAACUCUGAGCAACUGGGAGCCUCGCUCCCACCCCAGUGCCUGGAAACACAAACAGUAUUUUAUUGAGCCUUGGCUGCCGGGGCUCUGGUUUCAGGAAAAGCCUCAGUCCUGCAUUUGUGAAUUUUUAAGGAGGCAAACAAGGUGAAUUUGACCUUCCUAGGAGUGGGAGUUAGGGAAAAUUCAGGCUGCCCUACCAAGCCCUUGGAACCGUGCAGCAGGGGUCAGGGGAGGGAUGGGCAAAGGCGGUUUGGCCCAUGGAGCAGGUCUCCUGGUCCUCCCGGAGCACGGGGGGCGGGGAGCUCCAGCUCUUCAUCAAGCGCCCUUUGGGGUUUCCAACUGUUUUCUGUUGUUCUCUGUGUGUCUUUUCCCCUUUUGCCUGGGGGCGGGGGCUGGAGGGGAACAUACCUCUUAUCUACAUCACUCGGGUCUCAUGUCUGAAGGGCCUGUCUCACCUGCCACCUACCUGGCCUUGGCCUCGACAUCUGAGCGCCUCAUCACCUCCUCUCCACAUGCCCAGGGGUGCCCCUCCCAAGGCUGGCUGGGCAGGUCCCACGGACUAGGCCCCAGGAGGAGCAGUGGGCUUCCCCCAGGAAAGAGCAGAGCCAGCACUGCCUGCCUAGGGAGGGCACCCACUACCAGGCAUGGCUGGUGGCUCCGUUUAAAGAAAUCUUUGUCCAUGUGGGAGUGGGAGGUGCUUCCCCAUCCUGCCUGGAAGCCACGUCCUGGCUCUUACCGUGGACUCUGCAACAGCCGUGGUGGCCACAUGAAGAUGGAGGAACCUGGUGGCUCAGGGGCCCCUGAUGUCACCGCCUCCAAGGCAACGGGACUGGGCAGGGCAGCUCCUCAGGAAGGAUGAUCCCACCUGCACGGGUCAGCCCUGCAGGGGGACAAGGCCCACCACAACCCCACCUCAGGCCACCAACUGGACCUGUCCUGCCAAGAAGGUCCCUUCCAAUUUGUCCGGCAGCUGGUUCCCUGGAUACAGCCCAGACGCAGCAUCAUCCUCAUGUUCACCUCUGCUGUGCCCUACUUCCCCCGUAAAUGACAACUGUGUAGUCACCCACGCCGGGCAAGAGAACAUAGGUGCCACCUGGCGGGCCACACUUUUCAGGGGCCGUGCCUCGGGCAGGCCCGGCUCUCUGUUGUCCCGCAGCCCUCAGGGCUGGCGGUGGCUGCUCAGUGCCUAGGGAGUGCCCUUGCCACACAGCUGGGCAGCGAGCAUGACUCAGCGUUUACACUCAACCAGCCGCACAGGCUCCAGAGGGGAAGUUCUCUGGGGUCCUUCUAUGAGAGAGCAUCCUGUCUGCAGCCCUGUUCUGGCUCCUUCCACAUCAUUCAUGCAUUCAUCCCACGAGGACUAUGGUACCGUGGGCUCGCUCUAGGGAAGCAAGGCAGGAGCGCACUGGGGCUACUUGGAUUCCCGGGGCAGACACAUAUGUACCCUGCACACCCUCAAAUGAGCAAAGCCACCCCACUGGCCCCUGGGUGAGGCCAUGUGGACCCCCACACCUUUGGGGCCGGCUGGGCAAACCUUGAACCCCCAAUUUCUGCGUGGCCUUUGGCUGCCCUCCUUCUCCAAGGCGUGACUCUUACUCCAGAGACUCAGGCGAGCACGUGUCCCUUACCUUAUUUUCUCUCAAUCAAACUGAAACCCAUUGUGAUCCCCCAUAGUCCAGUGCGGUCUCUGUUAUUAUUACGGGUGUCUCCCUUCCUCCCCGUGCCCAGGACAGGCCAUGAGCCAGAGAUACAAGGGGCCCCAGGCAAGAUGCAGGGCUCUCUGCUCCUGGCUCUUUAUCGUCGUCGGGACACCCUUUGUCCAAACUCAAGGAAUCCCGGGAGGUCUGGCUUUGCCGCUUUGGCUGGGACUCAGGUACCUGGGCAUACCUGCAUCUGUGCCCCCUCUUCGUCCCAGUGAGACGGACCCUCAGUAUCCCCCCCAACAUAGAACAGGAAGGUCUCAAGCCAGCCCCCUCCUCCAGUUCAAUCACCCUCCCUCACAUCCACCCAGAGAAGUCCAGACCUGUGGCCACUUCCAUGCCCUCUCCAGACCAGGAGACACCUGCUGCUGACCUCGUGGAAAACUUAGAUUUUGACAUUCUGAUGCUUCGGAAGUGGUGGCUCCUCCUCCUUCACCCCUCCGCCACCUGUGGGCCUCCUCUCUGCAUCUCAAGAGAACAACCAGAUCUUUGGGCUCCUGGGGUGUGUGCCAUGCAAUUUAGACGAAGUGCUUUGAAAAUAUGCCAUUCAGUCUCUGACUAGGAAAAUAAGUCUGACCUGAUAGGUCCGAUGUCAUCAGCUCUUCAACAUGAGACAAAAGAGGGGAUUUUAUGUUUUGAGUCAUUAGAAUGAUAUAAUAAUUUUCUGAAUUGACAUCUGGAUGUUGAAAUUAGGAUGGUGCAAAAGGGGUCCAGGGCCUCAGGCUGGGCGCAGCAGCCAGCUCCCAAUGACGCAGAAGCUGCUUCAAAACCCCCUCAACAAAGAGGGGCACAUGCAAGUCACCAAAGUGGGAAGCCUUCACCAAGGCCACACCCAAAGUCUACUGAUUGUCUGUCCAAAGUUCGUUGAUUCCUGGCCAUGAACAAGCACAAUAGAAAAAGACACAGGGUCCUAGUGGCUACAAGUCAAUGUGAAUUGGCACAUGGUCUAGCAGUUUUAAAAUCUGACAGUAGAGUAUGGCAAUGGGCAAGGGCCAAGAAGUCCUGAGAUGGGAGGUCAGCGCUCUAACUGGGCUCAGUGGAGGUCUGUGACCAGUGUCUGGACACUAGCUACAGGGGACCGGGCAGAGGAUUCUGGGCAGAAGGAAAAUGUCUAAAAGUACUUUGGGAGGGUAAAGGACAGGGGCCUUAUUUAAAAUAAAGACUGAAGGAUAAUAAGUGUCA